AGUUCGGAUUACUUCUUUAAGUCUCUUUUCUCUUUUUUCGCGCAAAAAUGCCGGAUCCAGCGAAAUCCGCUCCUGCUCCCAAGAAGGGCUCCAAAAAGGCUGUUACGAAAGUGCAGAAGAAGGACGGCAAGAAGCGCAAGCGCAGCCGCAAGGAGAGCUACUCCGUUUACGUGUACAAGGUGCUGAAGCAGGUCCACCCCGACACCGGCAUCUCGUCCAAGGCCAUGGGCAUCAUGAACUCCUUCGUCAACGACAUCUUCGAGCGCAUCGCGGGAGAGGCGUCCCGCCUGGCGCACUACAACAAGCGCUCCACCAUCACAUCCCGCGAGAUCCAGACGGCCGUGCGCCUGCUGCUGCCCGGCGAGCUGGCCAAGCACGCCGUGUCCGAGGGCACCAAGGCGGUCACCAAGUACACCAGCUCGAAGUUAAUAGGACCCAUCCUUUGGAAGUAGGAAAGUGGCAUAGAAGGAGAAGCUGAGUUAGAGAUCACUCACCCACUUGCCCAUCAACUGGAACUGCAAGAGAUCAGAGAAUAAAGAUAUCAGUUGGUCCAAGGAAAAUAAUGAGGAAGAGAGAAUUGGGGAGACAGAAUUAAUGUAGACUCUGAGGGAUCAACUCAGAUCUCUUGAGUUUCUAUUUCUCUUUCUCAAAAUCCAGUACUAACAGAACUGAACAAGCUACAGGUGGUUAUCAAGGAAACUUCACUGCGGUGCGUCCAGGCUUAAUGCUACCUCAGGGUUGCCCUUCCCAUCCUUUUCAUAAAAUAAGCUCUAAUAAACCAUGGAAGCACAGAUACAAGUUGCUUCAUACUCAUGAGUUCUACCCAGAGUUACCACAGGAAGACAAAACUCUUGACUCACAACAGCCACAGCCUGUACCCUUCUAACUGUCCCCUCUGAGUCCAACUUACCCCAAAGGAGCAGAGUUGUCAAGAACCACAUGUUGUCUCCAAGCUGGUGGGAGCAGUGAAAUCUGUAACAUGCAAGAUAUUGAAGA